AGAAAAGGAAGUUGGUUUUCCAGAAAGCUGUAAUCAUGUCUUCUGUAUGACUUGUAUUCUUAAAUGGGCAGAGAGGAGCUAUCUAUAAGCAGCCUAUGUGAUUGAGGAUAGAGCAGCAGGAGGAAGCGAGAAAUUAGAAAUCGAGGAUCCUGAAUUCCCAAAUAAGGAAGGUUUCUUGUUCUUACAUUUAAAUGUGGGUUUGUCUGAGCUGAGAAUUUAUAAUGCUUCAGAAUAGUAGGGUGUGUUUUACUGAAAUCAUUAGGAAGAUUAUUUUUUUCUAUCAAAAUUGCCUUCUUAACUGAUACAACAACCUUAGUACAGAGCAUUCACAGUAAAACAUAUGCUCUGUUUAAUACACAUUACACUGUAAAGCAGUGAGCAAAUUCCAUUAAUUUUGUAGCUGUAUCAUAAAGCCAAUGAUGUUAUUAGACUACUUGGUUAUGAAACUGAAUUAGAUACUUUAAAAAUUAUUGAAAUGAAAGUCAGUAAUUCAAACAAGUGAGUCAUUGAAGGAUAUUUUGUUGUAUAUAAGGAAUCAAAAUGGUAAAUAAUUGAAGGAUAUUUUUAUUGUAUUUAAGGCAACAAAAUUUGAGAUAAUUUUCUUCAAAAUUAAAAUAACUUAAAAAUAGAGUAAGUAUUAGUUAAAAUUUCUUUACAUUAGUUUAAAAUGUGAACUUUUAAAACCUCACAACUUGGAAAUUUAAUUGUAAAUUUUACUCUGAAAACUAAAAACAUCUUUGAGACCUUUCUGGAUAGAUAUCUGCUGGAUAUAAGAGUGAGGCAUCCUUGGGAGUUCCUUAAAAUUAGGCCAGUCUGGGCCGGGUGUGGUGGCUCACGCUUGUAAUCCCAACACUUUGGGAGGCCGGGGUGGGCCAAUCGCUUUGAGCUCAGGAGUUCGAGACCAGCCUGGGCAACAUGGCAAAACCCGAUCUCUACAAAAAAUUAGCUGGGCAUGGUGGUGCGUGCCUGUAGUCCCAACUACUUGGGAAACUGAGGUGAGGCCAUCGCUUGAACCUAGGAGGUUGAGGUUGCAGUGAGCCGUGAUGCCGCUGCACUACAGCCUGGGCAAGAGGGUGAGACCCUGUUUAAAAAAAAAAUUAUGAUGGCUGAGUCUGUGUCAAAGAAAAUUAACUUAUUUUUUGGUGUUAACUAAAUUAUCUUUAGGUAAUUACAUUUUAUAUAGAUUGUGAUGAUAUAUGGCAGUAGUUUUCCUAUUACUACUACUUUUUUUUCUUGUUUUUCCUUUGUGUUUUUGUAAUACCAGUGGAGCCUUUUCUUAAAAUGAAACUAGGCAAACCUAAGACAAUUAUGCUUAAGGAAAAAAAAGGGGGGGAAUCUUACUCAGAACUGUUUUUUGAAACGGAUCAAAUGGAAUGGCUCAGAGCAGGUGUGAUGGCUCCUCCUGUAAUCCCAACACUUUGGGAGGCUGAGGUAGGAGGAUCGUUUGAGCACAGGAGUUCAAGAUGAAGCCUGAGCAACAUAGUGAGACCCUGUCUCUAUGAAAAAAGUUAAAAAAAAAAAAAAAAAAAAAAGCUAGGCACGGUGAUACAUGCAUGUAUCCCAGCUACUUGGGAGGGUAAAGUGGAAGAAUUGCUUGAGCCCCAGGAGUUCAAGCCUGCAGUAAGCUGUGAUCAGGUGACUGCACUCCAGCGUGGGCGACAGAGUGAAACCCUGUGUUAAAAAAAAAAAAAAAAAAGUAACAGCUUAGAUUAAAACUGUCAUAAUUCAAAAUUGUAAAGGAAGGCUGGGUACAGCAGCUCACGCCAUUAACCCCUCCAAGGCAGGUUGAUCGCUUAAGCCCAGGAGUCCAAGACCACCCUGGGCAACAUGGUAAAACCCCAUCUCUAUGAAAAAUACAAAAAUUAGCUGGGUAUGGUGGCAUGCACCUGUAGUCCCAGCUACUCAGGAGGCUGACAUGGGAGGAUCAUCUGAUCUCAGUCUGGGAGGCAAAGGCCUUAGUGACCCAUGAUAGUGCCACUGCACUCCAGCCUGGGGGACAGAGCAAGACCCUGUCUCAAAAAAUAAAAAAAAUAAAGAAAAAAUUGUAAAGGAAAAAAUGCAAUUUAGCUGAUGUCAGUAGAGGAAAUUUAAUAAAGAAAAAAUGAGAUUGUAUGAUUUGAGAGUCUUUGAAAGAUUUGAUGCAUCUGAUACAAAUUUCUUGAACACGUGACUUUCUUUGGAUCUUAGUGUCACAAAUCAAAAUAGCUAAAAUAAUGAAGUACUUGGAUUUCCAUCUACGUCAUAAACUUUGCAAAUUCCAAUAAAAAUUGUUAAGAACUCAUGUCUCUCACUUGUAUAUGUAUCAUAUUGUGGUUGUCUUUUGUUAAUUAACCAAGUUUUUUUGUUACUAAAACUAGUUGAUUACAAGACCUUACAUAAUAUUUAGUAUAUGCCACACUUUCUUCUAGGAAUUAUUUAUUCCCAUAAAAACCUUAGAGACACUGGCUUCAUGUCCUAUUGACCGUAAACCUUUUCAGGCAGUGUUUAAAUUCAGUGCAUUGGAAGGUUAUGUUAAGGUUCAAGUAAAAAAACAGCUGAGAGAAACAAAAGACAAGAAAAAUGAAAACUCAUUUGAGAAACAGGUCUCCUGUCAUGAAAAUUCUAAAAGCUGUAUAAGAAGAAAAGCCAUCGUAAGAGAAGAUCUAUUAAGUGCAAAAGUUUGUGACUUGAAGUGGAUACAUAGAAACUCUUUAUACAGUGAAACAGGAGGAAAGAAAAAUGCAGCAAUAAAGAUAAAUAAGCCUCAGAGAUCAAAUUGGAGUACAAAUCAGUGCUUCAGAAAUUUUUUCUCCAAUAUGUUUUCUUCUGUUAGCCACUCUGGAGAAUCUUCCUUUACCUAUAGAGCUUAUUGUACAGAAUUUAUAGAAGCCAGUGAAAUCAGUGCAUUGAUUAGGCAGAAGAGACAUGAACUGGAAUUGUCAUGGUUUCCUGAUACAUUACCUGGAAUUGGAAGAAUUGGUUUUAUACCCUGGAAUGUUGAAACAGAAGUCCUUCCUCUCAUUUCUUCUGUGUUGCCAAGAACUAUUUUUCCAACAAGUACCAUAUCUUUCGAACAUUUUGGUACUUCUUGCAAGGGAUAUGCAUUAGCACAUACUCAAGAAGGGGAAGAAAAGAAGCAAACUUCUGGUACAUCAAAUACCAGAGGAUCAAGACGAAAACCUGCAAUGACAACUCCUACAAGGAGGUCUACACGUAACACAAGAGCUGAAACAGCCAGUCAGUCUCAGAGAUCCCCAAUAUCAGACAAUUCUGGGUGUGAUGCCCCAGGUAACAGUAAUCCAUCUUUAAGUGUUCCCUCUUCAGCUGAGUCAGAAAAGCAAACAAGACAGGCUCCAAAACGGAAGUCUGUAAGAAGAGGAAGAAAACCACCUUUACUGAAAAAGAAACUUCGGAGCUCUGUAGCUGCCCCUGAAAAAUCAUCUUCCAAUGAUUCAGUAGAUGAAGAAACAGCAGAAUCUGACACAUCACCUGUGUUAGAAAAAGAGCACCAACCAGAUGUAGACAGUAGUAACAUUUGUACUGUGCAGACUCAUGUAGAAAACCAGUCUGCUAAUUGCUUGAAAAGUUGCAAUGAGCAAAUAGAAGAAAGUGAGAAGCAUACUGCAAAUUAUGAUACAGAGGAAAGAGUAGGAUCUUCAUCUUCUGAGUCUUGUGCUCAAGAUCUUCCUGUGCUAGUUGGUGAGGAAGGGGAAGUUAAAAAACUCGAGAAUACAGGUAUAGAGGCUAAUGUUUUGUGUUUGGAAAGUGAGAUUUCUGAAAAUAUUCUUGAAAAAGGAGGUGAUCCAUUGGAAAAGCAAGACCAGAUAUCUGGACUUUCACAAUCAGAGGUAAAGACAGAUGUAUGUACAGUUCAUCUUCCAAAUGAUUUUCCUACAUGUUUAACAUCUGAAAGCAAAGUGUACCAACCUGUAUCUUGUCCCCUAAGUGACUUAUCUGAGAAUGUAGAGUCAGUGGUUAAUGAAGAAAAAAUAACAGAGAGUUCCCUAGUAGAAAUUACUGAACAUAAAGAUUUUACACUAAAAACAGAGGAGCUUAUAGAGAGCCCCAAGUUAGAAUCUUCUGAGGGUGAAAUUAUACAGACAGUGGACAGACAAUCUGUUAAGAGCCCAGAGGUUCAAUUGCUUGGGCAUGUUGAAACUGAAGAUGUAGAAAUAAUUGCAACAUGUGAUACUUUUGGGAAUGAAGAUUUCAAUAAUAUUCAAGACUCUGAAAAUAACUUACUAAAAAAUAAUCUUCUGAACACCAAAUUGGAAAAAUCUUUAGAAGAAAAGAAUGAAUCGCUGACCGAACAUCCUAGAUCUACAGAGUUGCCUAAAACACACAUUGAACAGAUUCAGAAGCAUUUUAGUGAGGACAACAAUGAAAUGAUACCUAUGGAGUGUGAUUCAUUUUGCAGUGACCAAAAUGAAUCUGAAGUUGAACCAUCUGUAAAUGCUGAUCUUAAACAAAUGAAUGAAAAUUCUGUGACACACUGUUCUGAAAAUAAUAUGCCGUCUUCUGAUCUUGCGGAUGAAAAGGUUGAAACUGUUUCUCAACCAUCUGAAAGCCCAAAAGAUACCAUAGAUAAAACCAAAAAGCCUCGUACUCGAAGAUCUAGAUUUCAUUCUCCAUCUACAACUUGGUCACCCAACAAAGACACUCCACAAGAAAAGAAGCGGCCCCAGUCUCCAUCUCCCAGAAGAGAAACUGGGAAAGAAAGCAGGAAGUCUCAAUCACCAUCUCCUAAGAAUGAGUCAGCCAGAGGCCGGAAAAAAUCCCGUUCUCAGUCCCCAAAAAAGGAUAUUGCAAGAGAAAGGAGGCAAUCUCAGUCUCGGUCUCCAAAAAGGGAUACUACUAGGGAAAGCAGAAGAUCUGAAUCACUGUCCCCAAGAAGAGAAACUUCUAGAGAGAACAAAAGAUCUCAGCCAAGAGUGAAAGAUUCUUCCCCAGGAGAAAAAUCCAGGUCCCAGAGCAGAGAACGAGAAAGUGAUAGAGAUGGGCAGAGGAGAGAGAGAGAAAGGAGAACCAGAAAGUGGUCUAGGUCCAGAUCUCAUUCUAGGUCCCCCUCAAGAUGUAGAACAAAAAGUAAGAGUUCAUCAUUUGGUAGAAUUGACAGAGAUAGUUACUCUCCCCGGUGGAAGGGAAGAUGGGCAAAUGAUGGUUGGAGAUGUCCACGAGGAAAUGAUCGGUACAGAAAGAAUGACCCAGAGAAACAGAAUGAAAAUACAAGAAAAGAAAAAAAUGACAUCCAUCUAGAUGCUGAUGAUCCAAAUUCUGCUGACAAACAUAGAAAUGACUGUCCCAAUUGGAUAACAGAAAAAAUAAACUCUGGGCCUGAUCCAAGAACCAGAAAUCCAGAAAAGUUGAAAGAGUCUCAUUGGGAAGAAAAUAGAAAUGAAAAUUCAGGAAAUUCUUGGAAUAAAAACUUUGGUUCUGGUUGGGUAUCUAACCGUGGUAGAGGCAGAGGCAACCGUGGCAGAGGCACUUACAGAAGUAGUUUUGCCUAUAAAGAUCAGAAUGAAAAUCGGUGGCAAAAUCGAAAACCCCUCUCAGGGAAUUCAAACAGUUCAGGGAGUGAAUCUUUCAAGUUUGUGGAACAGCAAUCCUAUAAGCGAAAAAGUGAACAGGAGUUCUCAUUUGAUACACCAGCAGAUAGAUCUGGAUGGACAUCUGCAUCCAGCUGGGCCGUGAGAAAGACUUUGCCAGCAGAUGUACAAAACUACUACUCACGACGAGGCAGAAAUUCUUCAGGUCCACAGUCUGGAUGGAUGAAACAAGAGGAGGAAACAUCUGGACAGGAUUCUAGCCUAAAAGACCAAACAAACCAGCAAGUUGAUGGUUCUCAGCUACCUAUAAAUAUGAUGCAACCGCAAAUGAAUGUAAUGCAGCAACAAAUGAAUGCACAACACCAGCCUAUGAAUAUCUUCCCAUAUCCAGUGGGUGUUCAUGCUCCUUUGAUGAACAUCCAACGCAAUCCAUUUAACAUUCAUCCUCAGCUACCCUUGCAUCUCCACACAGGAGUGCCCCUCAUGCAGGUAGCCACUCCUACCAGUGUAUCUCAGGGACUACCACCACCACCACCCCCUCCCCCACCAUCCCAACAAGUCAACUACAUUGCUUCACAACCAGAUGGAAAGCAAUUGCAGGGUAUUCCUAGUUCUUCUCAUGUAAGUAAUAACAUGAGUACACCAGUUUUGCCUGCUCCGACAGCAGCCCCAGGAAAUACGGGAAUGGUUCAGGGACCAAGUUCUGGUAAUACUUCGUCAUCAAGUCACAGCAAAGCCUCUAAUGCUGCUGUAAAAUUGGCAGAAAGCAAAGUAAGUGUUGCAGUGGAAGCCAGCGCAGAUAGCUCGAAGACAGACAAGAAAUUGCAAAUUCAAGAAAAAGCAGCACAAGAGGUAAAAUUGGCCAUCAAGCCAUUUUACCAAAAUAAAGAUAUCACCAAGGAAGAAUAUAAAGAAAUUGUACGGAAAGCAGUAGAUAAAGUUUGUCAUAGUAAGAGUGGAGAAGUAAAUUCUACUAAAGUGGCAAAUCUGGUUAAAGCCUAUGUAGACAAAUACAAAUAUUCACGGAAGGGGAGCCAAAAGAAAACUCUGGAAGAACCUGUGUCUACUGAAAAAAACAUAGGCUGAAAUGGGGAACGCUGUCAAGGACAUUAUCAGGAUAUCUGCAAAGUGCAAUUUCAACAUGUACCAUUAACUGAAAAUCAUACAUAACUGUGAUUGAAAUUUGGUUUUGAUAAAAUUAUUUUUUUAACAUAGGAUAUGAUGUUUUGUUCUAAAUAAAUAUAGGUCUGCACUGCAACUUCUGUAUCCUUCCUUCCCCUCCACCCUCCCCCACAAAAUUCAAGGGAAAGUAAAGGGUUUAAAGGAAUGUGCAUCUUUACUAGGACUGUGUUAUAGUGUGGAUACUGGAAAAUGUAUAGCUUUUUGAUUAGGGCAAUGGAGUGCAUAAAUUAGAAACUUCUAAGUGCACUGGUUUUCAAAGAGAUAUAUAUAAUGCAUUUAUUCUGUCAGGUUAAAAUGUAAAGUAUGAUCUUUAUGAUUUUUUCCCUCUAAUUAUAGAAAGUUAAAUAAUGUAUUACCAUGAAAAAUGUUUCUAAUAUUAAAUAGAACAUAUCAGUUGCAAAGUUCCUAAUGUGUAUUUUUAAAGCACAUAUCUGAAUAAAUUGCCUAGAUAGAAAAAAAAUUAUCACGAGUAAAAUUUAGUGUUCAAAACAUUGAGACACUCUUCACCUAUUGUAUGACCAAAUAAAGGUUAUGCUGCUUGUUUUUCUUUUGUGCCUUUGUUUACCCCUAAUUGAGAUAAGCAGUUUGACUUACUAGAUUACAACUUUGGCAGUUCAAAGUCUUUGUUGAAGACUUUGAGGAAAAAGAUUUGGAAAAAUUGUUGACUUUCGGCCGGGCAUGAUGGCUCACGCCUGUAAUCCCAGCACUUUGGGAGGCCGAGGUGGCGGAUCACCUGAGGUCAGGAGUUCGAGACCAGCCUGGCCAACAUGGUGAAAUCCCGUCUCUACUAAAAAUACAAAAAUUAGCCAGGCGUGGUGGUGGGCGCCUGUAAUCCCAGCUAUGCGAGAGGCUGAGGCAGGAGAAUCAGUUGAACCCGGGAGGCGGGGAUUGCAGUGAGCCGAGACCAUGCCAUUGCACUCCAGCCUGGGCAACAGGAGCAAAUCUCCGUCUCAAAAAAAAGAAAAAAAAAAGUGUUGACUUUGUAGAAAUUAUGUUCUUUCAUAGUAUCUUCUUCUACCCGUUGCAGACGAUAAAUUAUUUGUGCCAAUUCGAGAAUUGCUGUUAGGCUGUUAUCCUCCCUUCCUUGGGGCUAAGAAUUACAAGACUCAUGGCACUGGCGUAAAGUUGUUGUUUAUCUAAUCACUGAUGAAAUAUUUUCACACUUGAAAAUCCCCAAAUGCUUUACAAUGAAUGAAGUGUUAAUUUGGUGACCAGGUGGUAGCCAUUAGCCAUGUUGCAAAAUUCUAGACAGUAAAACCUGUGUUUUAGAAACAGAGGGGAAAUUUAAAUAAUGGAGUCCUGGUUAGCCUUUCAGGGAUUAGGGAUUUGGGUUUUUUUUUUUUUCUCUUUUUAAUACUAGAAUAUCUCAGUUUUUAUAAAAGGUAAGUUUAAAAUGUUUAUUGUGCCAUUAUUUUAACUGGCAUCUUGAAAGAACAGUAGGUUUUCUCCAUGAUAAACUGAUUCCAGUAAGAAUUUUCAGUACAUACCAAGUACCUGGAAAGUUCUUCAGAUAAGUUAAUAGAUCCAAGGAGAUACAUGCCUCAGUGAGAUAAACUGACCUUUUUACUAGCUAAACUAUUUAGCCAGAGCAAUACUCUGUAGAACUGUGCUUUUCUAAAGUAAAGAUUAUCUGUUUCUCAAUUUUAUGUGCAUAAUACUUUUCCUGGUGCUAGCUUUGAUAGGCAAAAUAUUUUGAAAUGUUGGUCCCAUAAUGAUUGUGCUAGUUCAUAAGCUUUGUUGUUAUGAGUGUAAUCAUAAAAAUAUUUCCAAGCAGUUUUUGACCUUUAUUCUACAUUUCUGGGCAUUUGUAAUAUGGUAUUCUACUGGUAUAUAUUUUUAAAGUUUGCGUUUAGAUUAUGGUAAAGAAAUUUCAAGCAUAUUUCUUCUAAUAAAGUAUUAAGACAGUGUUUCAGAAUAUCAAGGCACACCUCCUUAGUUGUUUUAGAUUAGAACUCUAGAAACAAUUUUGUGAACAUUGAAAGUAUUUUGAGUUAAGCCUAAGCUGAUUAAUCACACAAUACAUACUUUUCCUGCAUUUUCUUUCAGUGACAUUUGAGAAUUGGGUGACAUUUUAAAAUGUGUUUUAUACCAUUUAGCUUUUGCAAACAAGUUCUAAAGUUUUGGAGAAAAAGUGAUGUGGUCAAGAGUUGAAGUCUCAUAUAUCUUUAGUAGCACUCCCAUGAAUUAUUUCCGUGACAGUAACAAGUGUGUGUUCCAUGUCUGAUUUGGGGCACUGGUUAGACUGCAUUAAUAGCUACUUGAUUAGAAUUCGAACUUUUAAAAUUUUGAAAUGUUUAAGAAUGUAUUAGAAAAUGCAUGCUUUAUGUUGAAAAAAUACAUUGCUUUAAUAUUCCUCAUUCUUGAGUUAAGAAAUUUAUGUUAAUUUUGCAUGGGCACAAACUUAAUCAGAAACAUUUUGUGGAGUUACAUUUCCUCUUAUUAUUUAUCAAGGUUCAGUAUUGAUCUUUGAAACCUUGGUCCCGUUAACUUACUAGUCACAUUGACCAAUGUUUUAUAGAAAUGCCUAGAAUUUUGAGACUAAUAGUAGUUAUCCAUUAACAUUCCAAAAGUUUUGUGCUUUUUAAAAUUUGUUUUGGUAAUUAUCACAUUUUUUUCUCUUACCUUCCUUUAAAUGGCCACAGUGUGUACUGCUGGAAUGUUCCAUCCAAAAGAUGUAGCUUCAGAAGCACAGUGAUUGCCCCAGGGUCCAUGAGAUAUUGUUUGUAUUAUGAAGUUGGAGUGCUGUCUACUGAAAUUAUACUCUUAAAUAAAUAUGUAUGUAGUGUGUAAUAUUUUCUAAUAAAUUCUUUUGAUAAACUAA